GUCUAAGAGGCAGACAGAUACAUUGUUCUUCACUGGUCAGCUGAAAGUCAAUUCAUCAUCAGUGAUAUUCAAAAAUCACAAGUCUUUGCUGGCAUGCCAAGUGCAAUAGAGGCAAUAUAUAUUAUUUUAAUUGCUGGUGAAUUGACCAUAGGGAUUUGGGGAAAUGGAUUCAUUGUACUAGUUAACUGCAUUGACUGGCUCAAAAGAAGAGAUAUUUCCUUGAUUGACAUCAUCCUGAUCAGCUUGGCCAUCUCCAGAAUCUGUCUGCUGUGUGUAAUAUCAUUAGAUGGCUUCUUUAUGCUGCUCUUUCCAGGUACAUAUGGCAAUAGCGUGCUAGUAAGCAUUGUGAAUGUUGUCUGGACAUUUGCCAAUAAUUCAAGUCUCUGGUUUACUUCUUGCCUCAGUAUCUUCUAUUUACUCAAGAUAGCCAAUAUAUCGCACCCAUUUUUCUUCUGGCUGAAGCUAAAGAUCAACAAGGUCAUGCUUGCGAUUCUUCUGGGGUCCUUUCUUAUCUCUUUAAUUAUUAGUGUUCCAAAGAAUGAUGAUAUGUGGUAUCACCUUUUCAAAGUCAGUCAUGAAGAAAACAUUACUUGGAAAUUCAAAGUGAGUAAAAUUCCAGGUACUUUCAAACAGUUAACCCUGAACCUGGGGGUGAUGGUUCCCUUUAUCCUUUGCCUGAUCUCAUUUUUCUUGUUACUUUUCUCCCUAGUUAGACACACCAAGCAGAUUCGACUGCAUGCUACAGGGUUCAGAGACCCCAGUACAGAGGCCCACAUGAGGGCCAUAAAGGCAGUGAUCAUCUUUCUGCUCCUCCUCAUCGUGUACUACCCAGUCUUUCUUGUUAUGACCUCUAGCGCUCUGAUUCCUCAGGGAAAAUUAGUGUUGAUGAUUGGUGACAUAGUAACUGUCAUUUUCCCAUCAAGCCAUUCAUUCAUUCUAAUUAUGGGAAAUAGCAAGUUGAGGGAAGCUUUUCUGAAGAUGUUAAGAUUUGUGAAGUGUUUCCUUAGAAGAAGAAAGCCUUUUGUUCCAUAGAGACCCCUAAAGAGUAUCCUGACUACAAGGAUGAAAGAAAUCA